AUUCUAGUGCAGCCCUGGUUACGCCUCCUCUGGCUCAGUCACACAGCGACGUAGAGGUGACUGGAGGUAUAUACUUGUCCUCACCUGGAUCAUGCUGAUGUGGCCCCAACCCCACCUCCCUACCCAUCCCCACCUCCCUACCCAUCCCCACCUCCCUACCCAUCCCCACCUCCCUACCCAUCCCCACCUCCCUACCCAUCCUAUGAUGUCCAAAGAAACCAGACAGAGCAAAUUGGCCGAGGCCAAGGAACAGUUGACAGACCAUCAUCCCCAGACCAACCCUAGUGUUGGUACAGCAGCAAGCGACACCAAAAAGAAGAAAAUAAAUAAUGGCACUAACCCUGAGACAACCACUUCUGGUGGUUGCCACUCGCCUGAGGAUGAACAGAAGGCAAGCCAUCAACAUCAGGAAGCCCUAAGGAGGGAGCUAGAGGCCCAGGUUCAUACCAUACGAAUCCUUACAUGUCAGAAAACUGAGCUUCAGAUGGCACUCUACUACAGCCAGCAUGCUGUCAAGCAGUUGGAAGGAGAGGCCAGGGAUCUGAUCAGCCGCCUGCAUGAUUCAUGGAAGUUUGCAGGAGAGUUAGAGCAGGCUCUCUCUGCUGUCGCUACACAGAAGAAGAAGGCAGAUAGGUACAUUGAGGAGUUAACAAAGGAGAGGGACGCCCUGAGUCUGGAACUGUACAGGAACACGAUAACUGAUGAGGAGCUGAAGGAGAAAAAUGCCGAACUACAAGAAAAACUUCAACUUGUAGAAUCUGAAAAGUCUGAGAUCCAGCUCAACGUAAAGGAGCUAAAAAGGAAACUGGAGAGGGCCAAGCUCCUGCUGCCACAGCAGCAGCUGCAGGCGGAGGCUGACCACCUGGGUAAGGAGCUGCAGAGUGUGUCAGCAAAGCUCCAAGCCCAGGUGGAAGAGAACGAGUUGUGGAACCGCCUGAACCAGCAACAGGAGGAGAAGAUGUGGAGGCAGGAGGAGAAGAUACAGGAGUGGGAGGAGAAGAUACAGGAGCAGGAGGAGAAGAUACGGGAGCAGGAGGAGAAGAUACGGGAGCAGGAGGAGAAGAUGCGGAGGCAGGAGGAGAUGAUGUGGGAGAAGGAGGAGAAGAUGCGGAGGCAGGAGGAGAUGAUGUGGGAGAAGGAGGAGAAGAUGCGGAGGCAGGAGGAGAUGAUGUGGGAGAAGGAGGAGAAGAUACGGGAGCUGGAAGAGAAGAUGCACGAGCAGGAGAAGAUACGGGAGCAGGAAGAGAAGAGGCAGGAGGAGGAGAAGAUACGCGAGCAGGAGAAGAGGCAGGAGCAGGAGGCGAAGAUGUGGAGGCAGGAGGAGAAGAUACGGGAGCAGGAAGAGAAGAUACGGGAGCAGGAGAAAAAGAUGUGGAGGCAGGAGGAGAAGAUUCAUGAGCAGGAGAAGAUACGGGAGGAGGAGAAGAGGCAGGAGCAGGAGGAGAUGUGGAGGCAGGAGGAGAAGAUAAGGGAGCAGGAGGAGAUAUGGAGGCAAAAGGAGAAGAUGCACGAGCAGGAGGAGAAGAUACGGAAGCAGGAGGAGAAGGUGUGGAGGCAGGAGGAGAAGAUACGGGAGCAGGAGGAGAAGAUACGGGAGCAGGAGGAGAAGAUGUGGAGGCAGGAGGAGAAGAUACGGGAGCAGGAGGAGAUGUGGAGGGAGGAAGAGAAGAUGCAUGAGCAGGAGAAGAUAUGGGAGGAGGAGAAGAGGCAGGAGCAGGAGGAUAAGAUGUGGAGGCAGGAGGAGAAGAUACGGGAGCAGGAGGAGAAGGUGUGGAGGCAGGAGGAGAAGAUACGGGAGCAGGAGGAAAAGAGGCAGGAGCAGGAGGAGAAGAUGUGGAAGCAGGAGGAGAAGAUAAGGGAGCAGGAGGAGAAGAUACGGGAGCAGGAGGAGAAGAUACGGGAGCAGGAGGAGAAGAUACGAGAGCAGGAGGAGAUGACGCAGGAACAGGAAGAGAAGAUGGGGGAGCAGGAGGAGAAGAUGUGUGAGCAGGAAGAGAAGAUGCAAGAACAGGAGGAGACGAUGUGGAGGCAGGAGGAGAAGAUAAGGGAGCAGGAGAAGAAGAUACGGGAGCAGGAGGAGAAGAUACGAGAGCAGGAGGAGAUGAUGCAGGAACAGGAAGAGAAGAUGUGGGAGCAGGAGGAGAAGAUGUGUGAGCAGGAAGAGAAGAUGCAAGAACAGGAGGAGAAGAUGCGGAGGCAGGAGGAGAAGAUGUGGGAGCAGGAAGUGAGGCUGCGGCAGCAGGAGGAGAAGAUGCAGGAACACUAGGAGCACCUGGAAGCUGCCAUCUAAUGAGCACAUGACAAGAAGGCAAAGACAAUAAACAUGUAAAAGCCGGCAGCAAGGCCUGGAGAAGAGUAAGCCGCCAUGUGACUGUUUAGAAUAUAGUCUGAGCACAAACCUGAAAAAAAAAUUUUAUUUAUUUUAAAUUGUGGCAAAAUACUGGCCAGGCAUGGUAGCUCACGCCUGUAAUCCUAGCAAUUUGGGAGGCCGAGGUAAAUGGAUGACCUGAGGUCAAGAGUUCAAGACCAGCCUGGCCAAUACAAAAAUUAGCCGGGCAUGGUGGCGCAUGCCUGUAAUCCCAGCUACUUGGGAGGCUGAGGCAGGAGAAUCGCUUGAACCUGGGAGGCAGAGGUUGCAGUGAGCUGAGAUCGUGCCACUGCACUCAAGCCUGGUGACAGAGCGAAACUCCGUCUCAAAAAAAAAAGUUUCUUCCUUACAUGUAUGUUUCUAUUAGUUUUCUUCUUGGUCUUUCUCAUUUAGUCUUGUGUUGUCUUUUGACAUUCAUAGUAAACUUUUAUCUGCCUCCAGAGAGUAUUGACUUUGAGUUUAUGGCACACAAUUGGAGUAAGGGCAGAUCGCCUUCAUCUACUUUGGGACUAAGCUGGUUCAAAGCAGGUUUUAGGUUUUCUGAUGGCUGGUCUAUGUUUUAUUCAUUUGGACUCCCAGGGGUGGCCCUUCCAGGGUCCCCACCAAGGUCCCAUCUCCUUCCUGGGACCCAAAUUCUCAUUAGGUCAUUUCAGCCCUGUGAGAGUGCCAAACAUUCAGCUAGGCUCUCCAGCCUCUUAACUACCACUUCAUACUCAGUUUCUUAGCCUCUUAGCCCUCUACUGUUGACCAAUCACCAAAUGUGGGAAAGCACUACAGACUGUCAGGAUCACCUCCUAGGCCUGGUCACUCAAGUCCUGACUGAGGUCUCCAAUUACCUUCCAACAAUUGUUUUUGAUUGGGGGCGGGGCACAUUUUUAUCCAGUUUUUCUAACUGCUCUUGUGGGGAGGCGAAUCCGUAACAAGCUCCUCUGCCUUUACUGAAAGUUGAAAACCUUCAUCUGUCCUUUUUUUGUUGUUUUUGAGAUGGAGUAUUGCGCUGUUGCCCAGGCUCUAGUGCAAUGGCACGAUCUCUGCUCACUGUAACCUCUGCCUCCUGGGUUCAAGCAAUUCUCCUGCCUCAGCUUCCCGAGUAGCGUGUGCCACCAUGCCUGGCUAAUUUUUUUUUAUACCUUUAAUAGAGGCAGGAUUUCACCAUGUUUUCCAGGCUGGUCUCGAGCUCCUGACUCAGGUGAUCUACCUGCCUCAGCCUCCCAAAGUGCUGGGAUUACAAGUAUGAGCCACUGCAUCUGGCCCAUCUGUCUUUUAAAACAUGUUUUUAAUUGGAGGUAUAAUUUCUAUUAGUGAAAUGCACAGGUCUGGUUUACAUUUUGAUGAGUUUUAACUCAUUUAACAUUACUAUGGAACCCACCUCCUUUGAAGAUACAGAGUAUUUCUAUCAUCCAGAAAGUUCUCCUGUGCUUUCAUGCUGUCCCGCACUCCCCCAGCAGCUGAUGAACAUGCUGAGGACAUUGGUACUGGAUUCUGGCCGCCCCAAAAGAGCCGCUUUGACCAGGCUUACCCAGCACUAAAUCCCUGCCUGCUCUCUCAAAAUUUCCAUCUUUAAACUGGUUGUACCUAUAACCCUCCCUCAUCAAGUCAAUAGAUAAACAAACCCUGAAAAAUAAACAACUCUUCCUGGCCCAGC